ACUCUGAGGCUCUUUCCAACGCUGUAAAAAAGGACAGAGGCUGUUCCCUAUGGCAGAAGCCUUUGUGAUCUCACCUGUUGGAAUGCACUAAUGUUUUCUGAGCCCCUUAAAUAUCUUGUCUACAUUCUUUUAAGAAGCUCUUCACCAACUGUCAGAAGGCAACCACAGAAAAAAGCCACUUAAGGUGUUGGAAUCCCUGGGCAAAGAUUUCCUCACUGGUGUUUUGGAUAACUUGGUGGAACAAAAUGUACUGAACUGGAAGGAAGAGGAAAAAAAGAAAUAUUACGAUGCUAAAACUGAAGACAAAGUUCGGGUCAUGGCAGACUCUAUGCAAGAGAAGCAACGUAUGGCAGGACAAAUGCUUCUUCAAACCUUUUUUAACAUAGACCAAAUAUCCCCCAAUAAAAAAGCUCAUCCGAAUAUGGAGGCUGGACCACCUGAGUCAGGAGAAUCUACAGAUGCCCUCAAGCUUUGUCCUCAUGAAGAAUUCCUGAGACUAUGUAAAGAAAGAGCUGAAGAGAUCUAUCCAAUAAAGGAGAGAAACAACCGCACACGCCUGGCUCUCAUCAUAUGCAAUACAGAGUUUGACCAUCUGCCUCCGAGGAAUGGAGCUGACUUUGACAUCACAGGGAUGAAGGAGCUACUUGAGGGUCUGGACUAUAGUGUAGAUGUAGAAGAGAAUCUGACAGCCAGGGAUAUGGAGUCAGCGCUGAGGGCAUUUGCUACCAGACCAGAGCACAAGUCCUCUGACAGCACAUUCUUGGUACUCAUGUCUCAUGGCAUCCUGGAGGGAAUCUGCGGAACUGUGCAUGAUGAGAAAAAACCAGAUGUGCUGCUUUAUGACACCAUCUUCCAGAUAUUCAACAACCGCAACUGCCUCAGUCUGAAGGACAAACCCAAGGUCAUCAUUGUCCAGGCCUGCAGAGGUGCAAACCGUGGGGAACUGUGGGUCAGAGACUCUCCAGCAUCCUUGGAAGUGGCCUCUUCACAGUCAUCUGAGAACCUAGAGGAAGAUGCUGUUUACAAGACCCACGUGGAGAAGGACUUCAUUGCUUUCUGCUCUUCAACGCCACACAACGUGUCCUGGAGAGACAGCACAAUGGGCUCUAUCUUCAUCACACAACUCAUCACAUGCUUCCAGAAAUAUUCUUGGUGCUGCCACCUAGAGGAAGUAUUUCGGAAGGUACAGCAAUCAUUUGAAACUCCAAGGGCCAAAGCUCAAAUGCCCACCAUAGAACGACUGUCCAUGACAAGAUAUUUCUACCUCUUUCCUGGCAAUUGAAAAUGGAAGCCACAAGCAGCCCAGCCCUCCUUAAUCAACUUCAAGGAGCACCUUCAUUAGUACAGCUUGCAUAUUUAACAUUUUGUAUUUCAAUAAAAGUGAAGACAAACGAA